GGUAACCUGCUCAGGUCCCCUUCCAUGCUGUGGAAGCUUUGUUUUUUUGCACUUUGCAGUAAAUCUUGCUGCUGCUCAUUCUUUGGGUCCACACUGCCUUUAUGAGCUGUAACACUCACCGUGAAGGUCUGCAGCAUCACUCCUGAAACCUGUGAAACAACGAACCCCCCGGGGAGAAACGAACAACUCCAGACUCGCCGCCUGAAGAGCUGUAACUCUCACUUCGAAGGUCUGCAGCUUCGCUCCUGAGUCAGUGAAACCACGAACCCACCGGAAGGAAGAAACUCUGAACACAUCCAAACAUCAGAAGGAACAAACUCCGGACACGCAGCCUUUAAGAAUUGUAACACUCACCGCGAGGGUCCGUGGCUUCAUUCUUGAAGUCAGUGAGACGAAGAACCCACCAAUUCCGGUAGGAGUAGGAAAUCACAUCACCUUCUUUUAAUCAGUCUCAAAUACCUGGCCCCUUGUGGAACCUGCAAGAGCCAGGUUUGGCGAAUGCAAUGAUAAGCAAUUGUCUAAUCACUGCCUUGAAAAAGAGCAGAGCAUUUGAGUAUGCUGUCUCCUCCUCUCCCUCACUUCAGUUGGGCCCAACAUGACAGUCUUAAUGGAAGCUCGGGGGUCAAAGGCUGGUGGCUUACUUCACGUAUAUUGCAGCAUUUCAGUACUGCUCUGCACGUGUGCUCCCCCGCCUGAUGAGCUUACUCCAGUGCCCACAGAUACGACAGAGUGUCCCAAGUGCCCCUCACACUCUAUUAGCUGCAUCCUUAACCUCUUUUUGCCACACCAUAAGCAUUGGGUUUUGUUUGUUUUGAGAUGGAGUCUUGCUCUGUUGCCAGGCUGGAGUGCAAUGGCGUGAUCUCAGCUCACUGCAAUAUCUGCGUCCAGGGUUCAAGCGAUUCCCCUGCCUCAGCCUCCUGUAUUAGCUGGGACUACAGGCGCACACCACCACGCGCAGCUAAUUUUUUUGUAUUUUAGUAGAGAAGGUUUCACGAUGUUGGCCAGGAUGGUCUCAAUCUCCUGACCUCGUGAUCUGCUCGCCUCGGCCUUCCAAAGUGCUGGGAUUACAGGCAUGAGCCACGGCGCCUGGCCAGCAUUGGGGUAUUUUAUUGAAGAUGGAAGCCAUGAAUGUUGAGAAAGCCUCAGCAGAUGGGAACUUGCCAGAGGUGAUCUCUAACAUCAAGGAGACUCUGAAGAUAGUGUCCAGGACACCAGUUAACAUCACUAUGGCAGGGGACUCUGGCAAUGGGAUGUCCACCUUCAUCAGUGCCCUUCGAAACACAGGACAUGAGGGUAAGGCCUCACCUCCUACUGAGCUGGUAAAAGCUACCCAAAGAUGUGCCUCCUAUUUCUCUUCCCACUUUUCAAAUGUGGUGUUGUGGGACCUGCCUGGCACAGGGUCUGCCACCACAACCCUGGAGAACUACCUGAUGGAAAUGCAGUUCAACCGGUAUGACUUCAUCAUGGUUGCAUCUGCACAAUUCAGCAUGAAUCAUGUGAUGCUUGCCAAAACCGCUGAGGACAUGGGAAAGAAGUUCUACAUUGUCUGGACCAAGCUAGACAUGGACCUCAGCACAGGUGCCCUCCCAGAAGUGCAGCUACUGCAGAUCAGAGAAAAUGUCCUGGAAAAUCUCCAGAAGGAGCGGCUGGCCUGCCAUGAGAAAUACCUCAAGAGUACUCCAGAGAAUUCCACAAGGCCCAGAAAUAUUCCUUCCAGAAGAAAACUAUACGUAAAUCUGCUCAGGAUAUUCAACAGCUAGCCAGUGCAUAUGACAUAUACUGGGUACUUAAGAAACGUUUGUUAAAUGAAUCAUGAUUAUAAAGAAAAAAUAAAUUAAAACUUAUGUUUAGUUAAACACUGUUUUGUGUAUUAGUCUAAUUUGUUUUAUCUGAAGAAAAGUAACAUAAGAAAGAUAAUAAAUGUGGAAUACAGAGGAAAUCCAUUCUGAGAGGUAAAUUCAUAGAUGUUAUCAUUCUAACAUUCUGAUUUUGCUUUAUUAAUGAUACCCAAAUGCUUCAAAAUAAUAAGUAGGUAUAAAUUUCUUAAUUUUGAGGAAAAUAUAGUACAUAAUCAGUGAAAAAUUAUACUUUUGUCAACUACAAACAAUUUUUACAGCUCAGGUCCCUGGGGAAAUGGAAGUGCUAUUAAGUGAUGGAAGAAAUGAAAGGGAAGUAGGUGUUAAAGGCUGAAAAGGAGGAUAUGUGUAAAAACGACUUCACUUCUGGAUGGUAGGGAACUAAUAUACAGCCCUCUUCCUGAAGGAAGAAGCAUUUAAUCAACUAAUUAGCCACAGCAGUUGGAUUUACUGGGCUAAGUAAAAAAUCCAUUCUCCCUCAAAGCAGUGCUGUGUAACAGAAAUAUAAAGCUAACCAGAUAGGUAAGUUUACAUUUUCUAGGAACCACAUUCAAAAAAUUAUUUUCAAUAAUAUACAUUUAUUCCCAUAUAUUACUCAAGAUAUCGUUUCAACAUGGAAUCCUUAAAAACUACUAGUGAGUUUUUUGGAAAUAUAACUUUGAAAUCUGGUAUGUACUUAACAUAUCUCAAUUCAGACUAGCCAAUUUCAAGUGUUCAGUAACCACAUUUGGCUGAUGGCUACUAUAUUAGACAGCACGGCUCUAAAACAAAGCUACUGAAAUCCAAAAACAAAAACAACAAUGAAAAAAUCUUUUUGCAAUAGAACUCUAAACUCUACUGUAAAAUAUACACAAGGACUCCUAAUGUAAAAGCUGAUUUCAAGAUUUCACAACGAUAAUCAUAAUGAUGAUGUAAUAACAGCUGACACUUAAAUAUAUCAGUACAAACCAUGCCCCAGUUAUGGUUUUAAGCAUGGUUUUUACUCAAUUCUCACAACAACCCUAUGGGGAUUAUAAUCUCUAUCUGUAAGAUGAAGAAACAAUCCCAGGCAACCAGGCCACAAGGAAAUAUUAUGCAUCUGAUAAAAUAGUAAAGGAGAAUUCUAUGUACUGAUAUGGAAAAAGAUAUUCUAAGUGUAUACAAAAGACCUUUAUAUUGGACAGUAAGUUAAAAAUCAGGUUGCAGAACAAAAUAUUUACUAUAACCUUCUUUUUCCAAAAGAAAAGCGCAAGAAAAUAAGAGACAUUCUCACACAUUUGUACUUCUACAUAUAAACUGUUAAUCAAUCACAGUUAUAUUCAUAUCAAAAAAGGUUUGGAAGGUUAGAAGCAAUGGUUAACACUGAUUAUCCUGGGAGAAGGUGAGUUUAAGUUAAAAGGUCUCUCUGUUUUAAAUUUUUAUCUUUUAUAUAAUUUUAAAUGUUUAUAUGCCAAUGCUGGCAGAAAGAAAAAAUAAUACAAACUUUUAAAAAUGGGAGAGCAAAGAAGGAACAGCCUUGAACUUGACACUAAUCCUACAAAUUCUGAAAGCACAGCAAAAGAUAUGGAGCAUCAGGGACCUUUGCCCUCCAAAGAUUUGCCAGAUAAAUAUAAUUUAAGAAUGGCUUUUUUGAGAGAAAUACAUAGUUUAGAAAAACAUUCAAAAUGUGCCUAUCUUACGUUAAUGA